AGAGGCGGCAAAUUGCAAGGAGACGCCGCCGCCUUCAUGCUGCCGGCGGGCUGCUCGCGCCGGCUGGUGGCCGAGCUGCAGGGCGCCCUGGACGCCUGCGCACAGCGACAAUUGCAAUUGGAGCAGAGCCUGCGCGUUUGCCGUCGGCUGCUGCAUGCCUGGGAACCAACUGGGACCCGGGCUUUGAAGCCACCUCCAGGGCCAGAAACUAAUGGAGAGGACCCCCUUCCAGCAUGCACACCCAGUCCACAAGACCUCAAAGAGUUGGAGUUUCUGACCCAGGCACUGGAGAAGGCUGUACGAGUUCGAAGAGGCAUCACUAAGGCCGGAGAGAGAGACAAGGCCCCCAGCCUGAAAUCUAGGUCCAUUGUCACCUCUUCUGGCACGACAGCCUCCGCCCCACCGCAUUCCCCAGGCCAAGCUGGUGGCCAUGCUUCAGACACGAGACCCACCAAGGGCCUCCGCCAGACCACGGUGCCUGCCAAGGGCCACCCUGAGCGCCGGCUGCUGUCAGUGGGGGAUGGGACCCGUGUUGGGAUGGGAGCCCGAACCCCCAGGCCUGGGGCGGGCCUCAGGGACCAGCAAAUGGCCCCAUCCGCUGCUCCUCAGGCCCCAGAAGCCUUCACACUCAAGGAGAAGGGGCACCUGCUGCGGCUGCCUGCGGCAUUCAGGAAAGCAGCUUCCCAGAACUCGAGCCUGUGGGCCCAGCUCAGUUCCACACAGACCAGUGAUUCCACGGAUGCCGCCGCUGCCAAAACCCAGUUCCUCCAGAACAUGCAGACAGCUUCAGGCGGGCCCCAGCCCAGGCUCAGUGCUGUGGAGGUGGAGGCGGAGGCGGGGCGCCUGCGGAAGGCCUGCUCGCUGCUGAGACUGCGCAUGAGGGAGGAGCUCUCGGCAGCCCCCAUGGACUGGAUGCAGGAGUACCGCUGCCUGCUCACGCUGGAGGGGCUGCAGGCCAUGGUGGGCCAGUGUCUGCACAGGCUGCAGGAGCUGCGUGCAGCGGUGGCGGAACAGCCACCAAGACCAUGUCCUGUGGGGAGGCCCCCCGGAGCCUCGCCGUCCUGUGGGGGUAGAGCGGAGCCUGCAUGGAGCCCCCAGCUGCUUGUCUACUCCAGCACCCAGGAGCUGCAGACCCUGGCGGCCCUCAAGCUGCGAGUGGCUGUGCUGGACCAGCAGAUCCACUUGGAAAAGGUCCUGAUGGCUGAACUCCUCCCCCUGGUAAGCGCUGCACAGCCGCAGGGGCCGCCCUGGCUGGCCCUGUGCCGGGCUGUGCACAGCCUGCUCUGCGAGGGAGGAGCACGUGUCCUUACCAUCCUGCGGGAUGAACCUGCAGUCUGAGCCUUUCCCAUGCUGCCCUCGGCCUGUUCAGAUGGGGAUUGGGGGUGUCUUCCCUGGCACUGUGCUCGGGGACCCAGAGAUGCCUGUGCUUCCCUGGGAAACCUGGUGAACUGGACCAGGUGGCCUCACUGGCUCUUCUCAGGACAACUAAGCCUGCUGGUCAGGGCUGGCUUUCAGCCUUCCUAAGGCUCCUGGACUCCAGAGGCCAGCGGGGAGCCUUUCCUGGCUCCCUCUGUUUUCUCUCACUGUAGACCAAAGAGCCGCUUGUGUGAUAUUAAAGCCACUUUAGAAAGCA